AGUCAGAGAGAAAGGGCCUCUUCAGUCUGUCUCAGGAGACUGGGAGAAACAGCAUAAAGGACCCCACAAGGAAGGGAGAGGUACCCUGGGUCAGGCGCUUGUGGAGAGAGGGCUUCGCAUGUAAAGUGACGUCAGGGAAAAUAGAACAGAAAAAAAGCCAGGGCCAGCCCAGAGGCACCUGAGAAGAAUCAGACCCACAGCUCAGCCCAGCCCUGGCACAGAGAAGAGACAGGCCUGGCAGCACCCAGGGACCCCCUUUCCUCAGCCUCCACCUGCAGGACAGCAGGAGCACUGAUGCGCUGAAGGUACGUUCUGGAGUCUGGAAGCAGCAGAACUGAAGGAAGUAAACACGGGUGUCUGGGAAGACCCCUCAAGCUGCAGUAAAGCCCAGGACUGAAUUGGCCACCUGAGGCCAAGGGUGGCACUCCAACCUCCUCCUAAAGGCUGGCUAGAGCCACAGGAAAGGGCCAGAAGCCAGAGAAAGGGCAAAGGUGGACCCCUGCCUCCAAACCUCCUCUGGAGACUGACCUCCUCUUUCCUGUGCCUUAUUGUUUCUCCCUCUUCUCUUUGUUCGCCACUGGGCGGUGACCUCAGGGAUCCUGGCCUAACCUGGUGAUUGUGCAGGCAACUGUGUCCGAGAAGACCCUUCUCUGGAAGAUUGAACCCCAAUUCAGCCAUGGUGACUCCUUUGAUGUCAAACUGGUAAGGGCUGAGCCGUGGGCACAGGAUACCACUCCUUCCAGCUCUUCUGCUGUGACCUGCCCAUGGAAGUCCCUGUGGACACGAAAUCCUGUUUGGAUCAUCUAACUGGAGGCUCUCUGUUCUUCACCUCCACGCGCCCUCUUGACCCCAGGAGGUUCAGGGGAGGAAGUACGCCACUCUCCACUGGCACCCUCCUUGGCCUACACAGAGUCACCCCUGAGCCCCUCAAUGUGUGCUGAGGUGGGCCCUGCUCUCUGCAGGGGUAUGGAGAGAAAUAGCUUGGGGUGCUGUGAGGCCCCGAAGAAGCUGAGCCUGUCCUUCUCCAUUGAGGCGAUCCUAAAGAGGCCUGCCAGGAGGAGUGAUAUGGACAGACCAGAAGGGCCAGGUGAAGAGGGCCCCGGAGAAGCUGCGGCCUCAGGCUCUGGGCUAGAAAAGCCUCCAAAGGACCAGCCCCAGGAAGGAAGGAAGAGCAAGCGGAGGGUUCGUACCACCUUCACCACUGAGCAGCUGCAUGAGCUGGAGAAGAUCUUCCACUUUACCCACUACCCAGACGUUCACAUCCGCAGCCAGCUGGCAGCCAGGAUCAACCUCCCAGAAGCUCGGGUGCAGAUCUGGUUCCAGAAUCAGCGAGCCAAGUGGCGGAAGCAGGAGAAGAUUGGCAACCUGGGGGCUCCACAGCAGCUGAGUGAAGCCAGUGUGGCCCUGCCCACAAAUCUGGAUGUGGCUGGGCCCACGUGGACAUCCACUGCUCUGCGCAGGCUGGCUCCUCCCACGAGCUGUUGUCCAUCGGCUCAAGAUCAGCUGGCCUCUGCCUGGUUCCCUGCCUGGAUCACCCUCCUCCCAGCGCACCCAUGGGAAACACAGCCUGUCCCAGGUCUUCCCAUCCAUCAAACUUGCAUCCCUGUGCUAUGCAUCCUUCCACCUCCACACCCCAAAUGGGGCAGCAUCUGUGCUACUUCAACAUAGAGAUUGGACAUGCUCUCCCCAAAUGAGCCACUUUCCUCUCCAGGUGAAGGCAGGUAGCAGAUGUGCCCUGGGCCUCUGGGGAAAUCGAUUUCACAAUCCAAAAAUGGCCCACAGCCCAGGAAGCUACCCUGAACAUGCCAGUUGGAAGGCUGCACCAGACUCAAAAGCAAACUAAACAAUAAAGGACAGCUCUCUUCUCUCCUGGCUAAAGCUGCUCUCCUGGUUCAGAAGACAGGCUGGAUGAGAUCUCAGGCCGAGCUCUGAAAUAGGGAGGUAAUCCUCCAGCACCUGUGUUUCCUCUAACUUGCUGUGUGACCUCCAGCCGGUCACUCACCCUCUCUGGACCUCAUCUGUAAGAGGAGCCAGCUGGAUAAGAUGAUUUCUGAAGACGCUUCCAUGGUGGGCACUGAGGCACAGAGGAGGCCAAGGAGAGGUUGUUUGUUCAUGCAUGCAUUCAUCCGUGACACAUGAGUACCUACUGAGGACUCCAUAAACAGAACGGGAUACAGAGAUAAACAAUUUGGGUUCUGUCCACGUUUGUCAAAAGGUGGUGCUGGCCCACCUCUGAAAGCAGAACACUUGCUCAACAACCUUGCUGUUGGCCCAAGUCUAACACAUUCUUUAUGACUGUGAGCAUCUCAGAGUGAGAGAAAAAUGUAGAAAGUUUUUUAAAUUCUAAACAGGAUUUAGUGUCUUUAGUUAUCUUGCUGGAUGGGAAAGGGAUGUUGUCAUUUCUGGCACAAAUGAAAAGUAGGACGGAAAGCUCCUUUCAUUCAGUUUAUCUUUCCAGGAUAUAUGAAAAGGGACCAGCUGGAAGACUAGCCUCACUCUGUCCUCGAAAGCCUGAGCUUUCAUUCAACUCCCUAUUUCCAUGCAAAGACGCUGGGCAAACCACAUGUUCUGUCUGAGCCUCAGUUUUCCUAUCCAUAAAAUGAAGGUAGCCAGGCCUGCCUCAAAGAGCAUUCAGGAGGCUCUGAGAGGACAUGAGAGUAUUUUGCAAAGUGAGGGCAAGGCCCAGUGUGGAGUGAUAUUGUUAUUCCAAGAUUCCACUGCAAAAGUGGCUGCUUUGGAUGCCAGCCCAGGAUGAGUAGUUCCUGUUCUCAGGGAGGUCAUCCGCUGAGCAUCCCUUCUGCACAGAUGUCUCUGAUUCUUGUCCUUGCAGGUGGAGGACAGGGCCUGCUCCCCUAAGCUGGGAAGCCUGGAAUGACCUCUUGCACAAGCCUAAAUUCCAGGAAUCUUCCCCAAAUCCCAGAUCCUCUGCAAUCUACCUGCACCCCUGACCCACCCAGGAGUUGGACCGGGAGUUGGGAAGCCUAGGUCUUAGUCCUACACUCCUUCUAAUUUGCUGUGUAACCUUACCAUUAAUCUCUCUGGGUCUCAGUUUUCUCAUCUGUAUUGGAGGUAGCAGUGCUAGCUCUGCCUUCAGGCAUGCAAUAUGCCAGAACUACAGACAACAGCCCACAGGAUGCAAAAGUGCUUUGCCAUCUUAAAAAUGCCAGAUCACUCAGAGCCUAUGAAUGUGGAUAUCAACACCAGGUCUCUAGCACCGCUGGAUGAAAGGAGAAGGCUAGAGGCUGAGGGAGGAAAGAGCAGUUAACAAACAAAGGCAGUAGCUCAUCACUUGGGUAGCAGGUACCCAUUUUAGGACCCUACACUCAAAUGUGCAAAAUAAAAUUUCUAUCAUUUUGCUAUAA